CUUUCCUAGAGUCUCUGAAGCCACAGAUCUCUUAAGAACUUUCUGUCUCCAAACCGUGGCUGCUCGAUAAAUCAGACAGAACAGUUAAUCCUCAAUUUAAGCCUGAUCUAACCCCUAGAAACAGCUUCCACGUGUGAGUGAGAACAUCACAGAUAUAGAACAAUGGAAGUGACAACAAGAUUGACAUGGAAUGAUGAAAAUCAUCUGCGCAAGCUGCUUGGAAAUGUUUCUUUGAGUCUUCUCUAUAAGUCUAGUGUUCAUGGAGGUAGCAUUGAAGAUAUGGUUGAAAGAUGCAGCCGUCAGGGAUGUACUAUAACAAUGGCUUACAUUGAUUACAAUAUGAUUGUAGCCUUUAUGCUUGGAAAUUAUAUUAAUUUACAUGAAAGUUCUACAGAGCCAAAUGAUUCCCUAUGGUUUUCACUUCAAAAGAAAAAUGACACCACUGAAAUAGAAACUUUACUCUUAAAUACAGCACCAAAAAUUAUUGAUGAGCAACUGGUGUGUCGUUUAUCGAAAACGGAUAUUUUCAUUAUAUGUCGAGAUAAUAAAAUUUAUCUAGAUAAAAUGAUAACAAGAAACUUGAAACUAAGGUUUUAUGGCCACCGUCAGUAUUUGGAAUGUGAAGUUUUUCGAGUUGAAGGAAUUAAGGAUAACCUAGACGACAUAAAGAGGAUAAUUAAAGCCAGAGAGCACAGAAAUAGGCUUCUAGCAGACAUCAGAGACUAUAGGCCCUAUGCAGACUUGGUUUCAGAAAUUCGUAUUCUUUUGGUGGGUCCAGUUGGGUCUGGAAAGUCCAGUUUUUUCAAUUCAGUCAAGUCUAUUUUUCAUGGCCAUGUGACUGGCCAAGCCGUAGUGGGGUCUGAUAUCACCAGCAUAACCGAGCGGUAUAGGAUAUAUUCUGUUAAAGAUGGAAAAAAUGGAAAAUCUCUGCCAUUUAUGUUGUGUGACACUAUGGGGCUAGAUGGGGCAGAAGGAGCAGGACUGUGCAUGGAUGACAUUCCCCACAUCUUAAAAGGUUGUAUGCCAGACAGAUAUCAGUUUAAUUCCCGUAAACCAAUUACACCUGAGCAUUCUACUUUUAUCACCUCUCCAUCUCUGAAGGACAGGAUUCACUGUGUGGCUUAUGUCUUAGACAUCAACUCUAUUGACAAUCUCUACUCUAAAAUGUUGGCAAAAGUGAAGCAAGUUCACAAAGAAGUAUUAAACUGUGGUAUAGCAUAUGUGGCCUUGCUUACUAAAGUGGAUGAUUGCAGUGAGGUUCUUCAAGACAACUUUUUAAACAUGAGUAGAUCUAUGACUUCUCAAAGCCGGGUCAUGAAUGUCCAUAAAAUGCUAGGCAUUCCUAUUUCCAAUAUUUUGAUGGUUGGAAAUUAUGCUUCAGAUUUGGAACUGGACCCCAUGAAGGAUAUUCUCAUCCUCUCUGCACUGAGGCAGAUGCUGCGGGCUGCAGAUGAUUUUUUAGAAGAUUUGCCUCUUGAGGAAACUGGUGCAAUUGAGAGAGCGUUACAGCCCUGCAUUUGAGAUAAGUUGCCUUGAUUCUGACAUUUGGCCCAGCCUGUACUGGUGUGCCGCAAUGAGAGUCAAUCUCUAUUGACAGCCUGCUUCAGAUUUUGCUUUUGUUCGUUUUGCCUUCUGUCCUUGGAACAGUCAUAUCUCAAGUUCAAAGGCCAAAACCUGAGAAGCGGUGGGCUAAGAUAGGUCCUACUGCAAACCACCCCUCCAUAUUUCCGUACCAUUUACAAUUCAGUUUCUGUGACAUCUUUUUAAACCACUGGAGGAAAAAUGAGAUAUUCUCUAAUUUAUUCUUCUAUAACACUCUAUAUAGAGCUAUGUGAGUACUAAUCACAUUGAAUAAUAGUUAUAAAAUUAUUGUAUAGACAUCUGCUUCUUAAACAGAUUGUGAGUUCUUUGAGAAACAGCGUGGAUUUUACUUAUCUGUGUAUUCACAGAGCUUAGCACAGUGCCUGGUAAUGAGCAAGCAUACUUGCCAUUACUUUUCCUUCCCACUCUCUCCAACAUCACAUUCACUUUAAAUUUUUCUGUAUAUAGAAAGGAAAACUAGCCUGGGCAACAUGAUGAAACCCCAUCUCCACUGCAAAAAAAAAAAAAAAAAAUAAGAAAGAACAAAACAAACCCCACAAAAAUUAGCUGGGUAUGAUGGCACGUGCCUGUAGUCCCAGUUACUCAGGAUGAUUGAUUGAGCCUUGGAGGUGGAGGCUACAGUGAGCUGAGAUUGUGCCACUGUACUCUAGCCAGGGAGAAAGAGUGAGAUCCUGGCUCAAAAAAACCAAAUAAAACAAAACAAACAAACGAAAAACAGAAAGGAAGACUGAAAGAGAAUGAAAAGCUGGGGAGAGGAAAUAAAAAUAAAGAAGGAAGAGUGUUUCAUUUAUAUCUGAAUGAAAAUAUGAAUGACUCUAAGUAAUUGAAUUAAUUAAAAUGAGCCAACUUUUUUUUAACAAUUUACAUUUUAUUUCUAUGGGAAAAAAUAAAUAUUCCUCUUCUAACAAACCCAUGCUUGAUUUUCAUUAAUUGAAUUCCAAAUCAUCCUAGCCAUGUGUCCUUCCAUUUAGGUUACUGGGGCAAAUCAGUAAGAAAGUUCUUAUAUUUAUGCUCCAAAUAAUUCUGAAGUCCUCUUACUAGCUGUGAAAGCUAGUACUAUUAAGAAAGAAAACAAAAUUCCCAAAAGAUAGCUUUCACUUUUUUUUUUCCUUAAAGACUUCCUAAUUCUCUUCUCCAAAUUCUUAGUCUUCUUCAAAAUAAUAUGCUUUGGUUCAAUAGUUAUCCACAUUCUGACAGUCUAAUUUAGUUUUAAUCAGAAUUAUACUCAUCUUUUGGGUAGUCAUAGAUAUUAAGAAAGCAAGAGUUUCUUAUGUCCAGUUAUGGAAUAUUUCCUAAAGCAAGGCUGCAGGUGAAGUUGUGCUCAAGUGAAUGUUCAGGAGACACAAUUCAGUGGAAGAAAUUAAGUCUUUAAAAAAGACCUAGGAAUAGGAGAACCAUGGAAAUUGAGGAGGUAGGCCUACAAGUAGAUAUUGGGAACAAAAUUAGAGAGGCAACCAGAAAAAGUUAUUUUAGGCUCACCAGAGUUGUUCUUAUUGCACAGUAACACACCAAUAUACCAAAACAGCAGGUAUUGCAGUAGAGAAAGAGUUUAAUAAUUGAAUGGCAGAAAAAUGAGGAAGGUUGAGGAAACCUCAAAUCUACCUCCCUGCUGAGUCUAAGUUUAGGAUUUUUAAGAGAAAGGCAGGUAAGGUGCUGAAGGUCUGGAGCUGCUGAUUUGUUGGGGUAUAGGGAAUGAAAUGAAACAUACAGAGAUGAAAACUGGAAGUUUUUUUUUGUUUGUUUUGUUUUUUUUUUGUUGUUGUUUUUUUUUUUUUUUGUUUUUUUGCUGAGUCAAUUCCUUGGAGGGGGUCUUCAGACUGACUGGUGUCAGCAGACCCAUGGGAUUCCAAGAUCUGGAAAACUUUUUAGAUAGAAACUUGAUGUUUCUUAACGUUACAUAUAUUAUCUUAUAGAAAUAACUAAGGGAAGUUAGUGCCUUGUGACCACAUCUAUGUGACUUUUAGGCAGUAAGAAACUAUAAGGAAAGGAGCUAACAGUCAUGCUGUAAGUAGCUACAGGGAAUUGGCUUAAAGGGCAAGUUGGUUAGUACUUAGCUGUGUUUUUAUUCAAAGUCUACAUUUUAUGUAGUGGUUAAUGUUUGCUGUUCAUUAGGAUGGUUUCACAGUUACCAUACAAAUGUAGAAGCAACAGGUCCAAAAAGUAGGGCAUGAUUUUCUCCAUGUAAUCCAGGGAGAAAACAAGCCAUGACCAUUGUUGGUUGGGAGACUGAAGGUGAUUGAAGGUUCACCAUCAUCCUCACCAACUUUUGGGCCAUAAUUCACCCAACCCUUUGGUGGAGCCUGAAAAAAAUCUGGGCAGAAUGUAGGACUUCUUUAUUUUGUUUAAAGGGGUAACACAGAGUGCCCUUAUGAAGGAGUUGGAGAUCCUGCAAGGAAGAGAAGGAGUGAAGGAGAGAUCAAGAGAGAGAAACAAUGAGGAACAUUUCAUUUGACCCAACAUCCUUUAGGAGCAUAAAUGUUGACACUAAGUUAUCCCUUUUGUGCUAAAAUGGACAGUAUUGGCAAAAUGAUACCACAACUUCUUAUUCUCUGGCUCUAUAUUGCUUUGGAAACACUUAAACAUCAAAUGGAGUUAAAUACAUAUUUGAAAUUUAGGUUAGGAAAUAUUGGUGAGGAGGCCUCAAAAAGGGGGAAACAUCUUUUGUCUGGGAGGAUAUUUUCCAUUUUGUGGAUUUCCCUGAUCUUUUUCUACCACCCUGAGGGGUGGUGGGAAUUAUCAUUUUGCUACAUUUUAGAGGUCAUCCAGGAUUUUUGAAACUUUACAUUCUUUACGGUUAAGCAAGAUGUACAGCUCAGUCAAAGACACUAAAUUCUUCUUAGAAAAAUAGUGCUAAGGAGUAUAGCAGAUGACCUAUAUGUGUGUUGGCUGGGAGAAUAUCAUCUUAAAGUGAGAGUGAUGUUGUGGAGACAGUUGAAAUGUCAAUGCUAGAGCCUCUGUGGUGUGAAUGGGCACGUUAGGUUGUUGCAUUAGAAAGUGACUGUUUCUGACAGAAAUUUGUAGCUUUGUGCAAACUCACCCACCAUCUACCUCAAUAAAAUAUAGAGAAAAGAAAAAUAGAGCAGUUUGAGUUCUAUGAGGUAUGCAGGCCCAGAGAGACAUAAGUAUGUUCCUUUAGUCUUGCUUCCUGUGUGCCACACUGCCCCUCCACAACCAUAGCUGGGGGCAAUUGUUUAAAGUCAUUUUGUUCCCGACUAGCUGCCUUGCACAUUAUCUUCAUUUUCCUGGAAUUUGAUACAGAGAGCAAUUUAUAGCCAAUUGAUAGCUUAUGCUGUUUCAAUGUAAAUUCGUGGUAAAUAACUUAGGAACUGCCUCUUCUUUUUCUUUGAAAACCUACUUAUAACUGUUGCUAAUAAGAAUGUGUAUUGUUCAGGACAACUUGUCUCCAUACAGUUGGGUUGUAACCCUCAUGCUUGGCCCAAAUAAACUCUCUACUUAUAUCAGUUUUUCCUACACUUCUUCCUUUUAGGUCAACAAUACCAAGAGGGGUUACUGUGCUGGGUAAUGUGUAAACUUGUGUCUUGUUUAGAAAGAUAAAUUUAAAGACUAUCACAUUGCUUUUUCAUAAAACAAGACAGGUCUACAAUUAAUUUAUUUUGACGCAAAUUGAUAGGGGGGCCAAGUAAGCCCCAUAUGCUUAAUGAUCAGCUGAUGAAUAAUCAUCUCCUAGCAACAUAACUCAAUCUAAUGCUAAGGUACCCACAAGAUGGCAAGGCUGAUCAAAGUCGUCAUGGAAUCCUGCAACCAAAAGCCAUGGGAAUUUGGAAGCCCUCAAAUCCCAUUCCUAAUCUGAUGAGUCUAUGGACCAAUUUGUGGAGGACAGUAGAUUAAAUAGAUCUGAUUUUUGCCAUCAAUGUAAGGAGGAUAAAAACUUGCAUACCAAUUGUACACCCUUGCAAAAUCUUUCUCUGAUGUUGGAGAAAAUGGGCCAGUGAGAUCAUGGAUAUAGAAGUACAGUCAAUGUUCAGCUGUACCCUCCCACAAUCCCACUUCCUUCCUCAACACAAUUCAAACAAAUAGACUCAGACUGUUUCAGGCUCCAGGACAGGAAGUGCAGUGUAGGCAAAAUUGCAAAAAUUGAGGGCACAGGGGUGGAGGUGGGGGGGUUGAAUAACAAGCUGUGCUAAAUAAUUACGUGUAAAUAUAUUUUUUCAUUUUUAAAAAUUGAUUUCUUUUGCACAUUCCAUGACAAUAUAUGUCACAUUUUUAAAAUAAAUGCAAAGAAGCAUACAUCCAA